GCCCCGCCGGCCCCGCCAACGUGACGGUCAGCCCCGCCGAGCGCUCGCACCCGCUCACACUCAUGAUCACUCGCACACUCGCUCCAAUACGUGUUAAGGCGCGAUCGCGGGGUCCCUGGCAGCCUUCGCUGCACCCUCCCCCCCACAGGGGUACUCACAGUUGCCAUCUGCAUAGGGGGCAACUUUCUCCGACCCAGCUGUGGCCGCCGCCCCCUCCAGCCUCCUCUGGCUCCUCGCACCCUCCGGCCUGGGUUCGCGCCGGCCGGCCCUCCCCUCCCCCCUCGGCUCUCCUCCUCGCCGUCUUCACCACAUUCCCCCCUGGUCAGUGGCGCACGCCGGGGGACGAGCCAGAGGGAGCGGGUCGCGGGGGUGUGCAUGCAUCUCCCGCCUUCUUCUUGCAGCGCACACUGUACAUGGUAGUGAGGGGGCGAGCAAAGGUGGCACCGGCCCCUCGGCUGCUCCAGCGAAGGCGGCGGCUGCAGCUCCUGCGCUGUCCUCCGCCCCCCAGCGCAGCGGCGACCACCGCGCUGGGAUCCCGCCGACGCUGUCUCCGCGCCGAGCCCGCCGCCGCCGCGGCCCCUAAUUAGUAUUUGAGAGGCUCUUGCAUCCCUUUGGCAGUUUCAUCCUCACGGUGUUUGCAGGGUUUUUUUCUGUAUCCCUUCCCCAGAUGCGGCGCACAAUCGUCAUUAGUUGGAACUCUCUAUCACCGACAUCCUUUGGGGUUUCUGGGGGAAGGGGGGGGCGGGCAGCAACCGCGUCGUUCUAUGCCUGUGGCUUGUCCUGGCAGCCCGGUGGCUCUAAAAAAAACUCCGAGAAAGUUGCGUCUUCCUCCCGGGCGCCGAGGAGGUGGCAACGCGGUAAGCAACACCGGGUCUCUGAGACAGCUGCUCCGGAGCGGGUGCAGGGCCCAGUCCAGUGCACUUGUUUAUUGUCGCGCCUCUGGUGCGAGCCAAGCUGCAGCAGACAUGAUGGGCCCGGGGCGAAGCGGGCGCUCGGUGGCCGAUAGAUGGCAGCCGAGGGCGAAGGCGUCCCUGGGCUAGGGCGGCGCAACCGGGGCCCCCUUGGAUGUCACAUUCGUAGGAAGAGAGAGAAGUCUUGGACCAUGUGUGUAAUUCGAGCGUGGGACUGUGCAAUUCUCGGAUUGGGAAAGGGAGGAGUGGAAAUAACCCCGGCAGUGCCAGGCUUGCUGGUGGUCAGGAACAGAUGAUUCCAGCCCUGUGCUGAUCGCCUGCCUUCCUCCUGCCAUUCAGAAUGCUGCUGUCUCGUGUACUUACUGUUAAGGAUCCUGGAAAAGGGAGUGGUUCCUCCUAGCUGCAAACAAGGGCGCUACUUUUCUUUUCUCUUUAAUAGAAUUACGUUUUAUAGGUGUGUCUAGGCAACACAAGGGAAUGUGAAAGACUUUCAGAGGGAAUGUUUGUGAAUACAUCUGGUGUGUACUAAAAAGCUGGAAAACCCCUAAGUAAAUGCAAUAUCGAUAGAAAGCGAGUUUCUUGAAGAGUCAUCUGCUAAACUCCACUAGAGUCAUCUCUACAGGUGUGGUUAAGAGAAAAAAAAAUUGCCAUUAAGGAAUCAGCAAAUAGGAUGUCUGAAGUGAGGAUAUAGCACCUAUCUCUGAGAUUAAAGUCAUCUGAUCAAAAAUGAUGCCUCUGAGACUAUAACAAAGGAAUGAAUAAUGAAAUAUAAGAAUGGGGAUUCUGCACUAACUCUAUGGGGAAGAAAACAAUGGUAAGAGCAAAAGGAUCAACAGCAGCAACUCCUGUUUCCAUCGAUUUGUUUAUAAGAUGCCGUCUACAUUAUUCCAAAAUAUCCCAGCCUUUUUCUCCCCUGUCAAGCUUCCCUGUCUCUAAAAGAGAUCUUGCUCUUCCUGCACAGAAAGAAAUAAUAAUAUAUCACUGAAAUAUUAUUAUUACAUUUAAAGUUACUUACACUCUUUCCCAUUCCUAUAAUUUCCUAGUUGGAAGCCCUCGCACUUGGGAAAUUAUUUAAUGUGAUUUUUUCUCCCUGACAUAUAAAUUGUCACAUCACCUUAAAUGUUGGGACUUCAGGUUGGGAAGUGGGUGGAUAAUAUUCUUGAGGAAGCUGCCUUCCUUUUAUAGAUAAUGUUACCUCCUUGUAAAGGUUGCUUUCUAUGUAUUAUUCUACUUUUUUUCUAAGAAUAUACCAUAUAAUGAAAACUUUACAGGCUUGACAUCCUAUUACUAAGAUUAUAAUUGUUGAGGUCUUCAAUAGAAUUUCAAGUCAAAUAUGUUGUGCUAUAUGCCUACUUACAUUUCACUCUUUGAUUCACCUAGUUAGGAUCUCAGAAUUGAACUUUAAUUGCAGAUUUAUUACUUCUUUACUCUCUUCAUGUAUUAAUUUAAAAUUUACUUUUUCCUACCUUCAUCUUGGUUUGAGAAGGUUAUUUCCCUUUCAUUUGAUUUAUUUGUUUUAAUUUACAUGUGCAUAUUUAUUACCUGUAUAUAAGCAAAAUUUAUAGAAGAGGAUAGUAUGAGUUAAUAAAUAAGUAUAUUAUCAGGAUAUUUUCUUUAUAUUUAAUAUAUGUUGUAAUUAAAAUGCACUGUUUAGCUGAACUGUGCCUCCUGGAAACUGUAGCAUUUAAAGACAGCACUAUGUGAAAUAUAAAAUUAUGUUUUUUUUCUCUGUGUCUAUGAUUUAUUGAAGUAAUGUUCUUCAGGAAAAUUUUUUUAAUUUUCAAAUUUAUAAUUGACAUAAUAAUUGUACAUAUUUAUAGGGUACAAUGUGAUGUUUCAAUGCAUGUCGAUAAUAUAACGAUCAAAUUGGAAUAAUUACCAUAUCUAUCACUUUAAACAUUUGUCAUUUUUAUGUGACAGGUGACAGCAUUUAAAAUAUUCUGUUCUAGCUAUCUUGAAAUAUACAGCAAAUUGUAGUUUGCUGUAAUCAUCCUUCUGAAAUUAAUUUUUUCUGAGUUUAGAUUUUCAGAACACCAAACUGGUAACCAAAUUAUUAAUCAAAUUGACAGAAAAUUUUAUUCUUGUUAAUAAAAAUACCAAUUUAUAUUUA